GCAGUGGUUGCUGGGCGACCACGGAGAGAAAGCCGGGACUUGAGGUGGGAACCCCGGCUGGCGUCCGGUAGGGGGAGGUUCCCGGGGAAGCCCGCGGAAGGCGAGGUGCCUGGCCUGCCAUGUAGGGGCUCGUUCCAAGCCGCAGACCCCACCGCCCUCCCUCUCCCCGGGGCCCAUGGCGGUGGCCGUGCCCCCGGGUCGGGCCGCAGGCUCAGGCUGGGCCUGGAGGCCAGUGGCGCGGGACGCGCUUUUGGCUAGAGCUUUCCAUUCAUGCACCGAACUGCGGGGACGGUUCUAUCUCGUAGGUGGUCUCCUAGCAGGAGGAGCGAGAGAGCCCAGCAGCGAUACGGUGGUUUUCGACCCAGCUAGGGGCCAGGCCGUACGAUUGGGAGCCCGGGGCAGCCCCCCGCGCAGUCACCACGACGCGGCACCCGUGGACGGGCGUUGGCUCUGCGUGGUGGGCGGCUGGGACGGGUCUCGCCGCUUGGCCACAGUGACCGCACUGGACACAGAGCGCGGUGUGUGGGAGGCGUGGACAGGGACCCCUGGUGACUGCCCCCCCGCCGGCCUCAGUAGUCACACCUGCACCCGAAUCUCUGACCGAGAGCUGCAGGUGGCUGGCCGGGAGGGCGGUAUCCACACUCAGCGACGCUAUGGAAGCAUCUACACAUUAAGGCUGGACCCCAGCGCCCGCACCUAUUGCUACAAGCAAGAAGGCUGCCACACAGCCUCACGCUCAGGUCACUGUGCGGCCCUGCUCCAAACUCCUGGACCCCAUCCAGGUCAUCAGCUAUUGCUCUUUGGAGGUUGCAACUUAGCUGAACCAGAAGUAGCUGGGCAUUGGAGUCAUGGGAAAAUUAAGUCCUUUCUUUCUCCCCAAGGAGGAACCACCUGUUGCUCCUCAUUUGAUGGAACAGCUUGCAAGGCUUGUGAGCAGUGGGCAGGGGUCCCAGAAGGGGCCCCAUGGACUACGGCAUCACUCAUGUUCUGUGGUCGGGCCCUUUGCUGUGCUGUUUGGUGGAGAAACUCUGACCAGAGCUAGAGACACCAUCUGCAAUGAUCUCUACAUCUAUGAUACUCGCACAUCUCCUCCUUUGUGGUUCCACUUCCCCUGUGCAGAUCGUGGGAUGAAACGCAUGGGCCAUCGCACCUGCCUUUGGAAUGAUCAGCUUUACCUGGUUGGGGGUUUUGGUGAGGAUGGCAGGACAGCCAGUCCACAGGUUUGCAUCCUGGACUUUAUCUAAAUAGUGCCAAGACACAUCACUAAGCCUCGUUUUGUUUUGCUUUGUUGCAAACCUAUAAAGCGUUAUCACCAGAGCUAUCUGCUUCACUUCAAAUGCUUAUUAAAUUUCAAUCUGAGACUCAA